AUUGUGGCGGUGAGGAACAGGAAGCCCUGAAGGGUCAAAAGAAAUACAAAAGCAAAGGCUAUUUUCUUUUUUUUUUUCUUUCUUUCAUUCAUUCCUUCCUCUGUUUCUUUCUUUCUUCCUUUCAUUUUUUUUUCUUUUUUAAGAGCGAGCGGCUCUGCGGUGGCGGUUUGGGGUGGGCGCCGCCGAGGUGAGGUCGUCUCGCCUCCCGCGCGCCGGUAGGUGAGUGCGGCCUCGGUCCUGGCCUGGCGGCGACACCUGGGUUCCAGCUUCCUUACGGAAGAGAUGAGCUGCGGCUGCUGUUAGGGUUAGGGCCAGGCCUGUUCUCAGUCCGCGCACCCGCUCCUUGUCCGGAGUAGCCGAAGCCUGGGGCUUGCGGGCCCAGCCUGAGGGGAGCUGAGGGUGCCCGCGGGAAGGCAUCUGGGUCGCGGCGAGGACCCUUUCAGGCGGGCCCAACACUGCCGGGCGUUUAAUGGGGUUUCCCCAAUUUUCUGCUAGGUAGGGCCACCCAGGUUUCAAGUGAGUAGCAGGCUCCGUUCCAGAGGUCUUGGAACAGGUCCAGGUUACUCACUCGGAUGUGCGGCGUCUGGUUGGAAAUGGUUGAAUCCCAGAAUGGCAGUGCAGGAUGGGAAGCACAUUUAUUGUGUGCCAUGUACCAGUUGCUGUGCCAAGCGAAUUUUCUAUUACGGAAAACAAGCCAGCUGGCCCGUUUUGCAGAAAACUUAAGAAACAAAGAGAGUUGAAGCGUCAUGCUUGAGAGUUGGUGGUCCUUGUGACUGUCAGUCCACACAGAGGAAAGGGGGAGACCUGUUUGUUCGUAGUCGUGGUUCUUUAAUGUUAGUGGAAAACAAGAUCUCCUGGGGCCCUUUUAAAAUGCAGUUUCUCAGACUCCCGCACGCUCGGGUAGCCCGACUGGUUAGUUCAGGAGUGGGACCCAAGAAGCCAGAUGCGAGCCUGGUGAUCGGAAUUCCCGAUGACCUCUUGCCUACCACCUGUGACAUAAGAUUUGUCGAUUCAUCAGUUAUUUGGUGUAUUCAUGUGUCCACAGGGACACCAUAAAAUGGAAGGCACCCUUCUGAAAUAUUUGAAGGGAAUCAGUGGGUAGACUCCUUUUUGAUACAAAGUAUUGAGCCGACAGCAGCUUUUACAGUCUUUUAGUUAGAUGACCUGCGAACAAUUUGUAAGGAUCUGAAAGUAGAGGCUGCCCGAUUAUCUUUCUCAACUGAAGUCUUCAUGUCCUUACCCUGUGGGGAAGUGCUUCAUGAUAUAAGAAAGGAAUAAUUGUGUCAAAACCAUUUAGUUGAUUAUCAGUCUUCACUUUCAUCUUCCAAGAAUGGUGAUGCUUGGUUAGAAUCAAGCUGCUGCUUUAGCUAUUGAAAACCACGUAUGUGGUAAAUCAAGUAACAAGUGCGAUGUACGUACAGGGUCAGUCAUAGUGUAAUUAUGCCUUUAUGGCAGCUAAAUUAAGCAUUUUCAACGUGUUCACCAUUAGUCACCUUUUGAACAUACUUUGUCUUCAUUCUUAAAUAUUAUGUUUCACUCUUUACUAUAGAAUAUGUUGUUAAGAUUGUUUUGUCUAAAAUCAAGUAUCGACAAGUUUAAAAAAAAGAUUGUUUUGUGUUUGGUUUUCUGUAUUUCCACUAUGCUCUAUGGAACUAUGGGUUUGUUUUUGUUCAAUUUGUUUGGUAUUUAUUAGACUUCUUGAAUCUGUGGAUUAGUGUCUUUCAUUAAUUCUGUAAAAUUCUCAGCCAUUUUAUAUGCAUAUAUUGCUUCUUCCCAUUGUUUCUCUUUUUUUUUUUAUCGAUUUAACUAAACCUUUUCACUCUUUUCUCUAUGUCUUUUACUCUGUUCUUUCGUAGUACAUUCUGGAUAAUUUAUUCUCAAGUUAUUUCCAUUGUUAUUAAACUCGGCCUCUGAAAUCUUAAAUCAUAUAUUGCAAUUUUUAGUUUCUGAAGUUCUGUUUGGUUUGUGACACUUUUACAGUUUUUUAUUUCUUACUAUUUUGAGGCUUAAUUUUAUUUCUUUAAACAUGGAAAGUAUAGUUGUUUUUAUAAUCUCUAUGUUUAAUUCCACUGUCUGAAUUCCCUUUGGGGGAGUCUGUUUCUGUUGUCCAUUAUUCCUGCUGUUUUACUUCCCAGUUCACCUUUACUUUGAAGCUGUAGUUCUUUUGGGCACAAGAUUAAGAUGGAGAGGGAGGUAGUUGUCAGACUCCACUCCCUGGAUGGGCUCCUGGCUUGAACUUGUUUCUGUUAUCUCAUAAAGGCACUGAAACUUUAGCUUUUAGGUCAGAGAAGUCCUCAGGAUGAAAUCCAUUUUGAAUAUUGGGCUUAAUUUCUGGUUUUCACCUUCUAGAUUGUGUCCAAAUUCUUUACUAUCUUGUUAGCUUUUCUAUUUAAGAAUUAAUAUUUUUGGCUGGGCGUGGUAGCUUACACUUGUAAUCCCAGCACUUUGGUAGGUCGAGGUGGGCAGAUCACUUGAGGUCAGGAGUUUGAGACCAGCCUGGCCAACAUGGUGAAACCCUGUCUCUACUAAAAAUACAAAAAUUAGCCAGUCAUGGUGGCGGGCACCUGCAAUCCCAGCUAUUCGGGAGGCAGAGAAUAAACAGCCAUUGGACUCUUCAAACAAAAACGCUGUCUCCAUCAAGUACUGCUUUCGCAGGAUAAGUGACCAUUUUUAAUCAGUUGAAAUUAACGGAAAGUAGCAGUUAUUUUUGAAAGAUGACAUCAAUUAUAUAAUAUAGUAAAGAGAUUUAAUUUUUAGUCCUUUGUUUCUUACUGCACAAAUUGUAUGGCGUUUGAAUAGAAUUCCCAUGAUACUGACACUUCAGCAAAUACUUGCUUGAUGGCUACCAAUCUCUAUAACUUACAUUGCACAGUACCUAGGAAUAUUCAUGUGAGUUCAUUCCUCCCUGCUCAGAUUCUUCAGCUCCUCGUGGUUGGUUUAUUCAGCCGGGUGCAGUGGCUCACACCUGUAAUCCCAACACUUUGGGAGGCCAAGGCCGGUGGAUCACCUGAGGUCAGGAGUUCGAGACCAGCCUGGCCAACAUAAUGAAAGCCCAUCUUUACUAAAAAUACAAAAAUUAGCCGGGCAUGGUAGCACACACCUGUAAUCCCAGCUACUCAGGAGGCUGAGGCAGGAGAAUCGCUUGAAUCUGGGAAGCGGAGGUUGCAGUGAGCCAAGAUCGUGCCACUGCACUCCGGCCUGGGCGGCAGAGCGAGACUCUGUCUUAAAAAAAAAAAAUUAUAUAUAUAUAACAAGAAUGAAGAGAGACAUUUACUGGGACACCAAUGGCAUUGCCGUAUCCUAGUAUUUAUUUCCCAGGUUUAAAUCAUAUCUAAUCUGAUAAAUUCAUUUCCUUCAGACAUGAUUAUUUUUCUCCAUCUUAUAAAAUUAAAGUAACUAGGAAUGUUUGGCUCAGAAAAGCAACAAAUUAGGAGGAACAUGGGAAUUGUCUUCAAACAACUGAAGUAUGGUCAUGUUAGAAAAGAUUUGAUUCUUUUUGUAUAGUCCCAGUGGAUUGAACCUAUGUAUUGAAUUUAUAGUAAAACAGAUUUCAGUUCAGUUUAAGGAAGAACUAUCCUAACAGUCAAAUCUGCUUAGAGAGGGAGUUGGCUGCCUAGGAAGGGAAUGCAGUGGUCCCUCUUGAAGUUUUAAUAUAUGAGUUGGAUGACCUUCUCCUGGGUGUGUAUGGUAAAUUCAGAUGUCGAGUGGAUUAUCAUAUUAGGUGGGCUAUAAGGACUAUCCCACCCUGAAUUAUUUACUAGGAAAAAUGGGUGAUGGAAAGAAACCAGAUGAUUAAUACAGGAUGAGAAAGGAGACACGGUUAAUAGGGGAUAAGAAAGGGGGAAAUUGAGGGUUCGGAAUGUCUCUCCCAACCAUUAGAGCCCUAGAAAGUUCACGUUUUCUCUGCCAGAGACAUUUAAGAAAUUGUUGGCUCUGGUUUCAUAAGAGGUUGUUCUGUAGAACUUGAGGAAUUUUUGGCAUUUUCACAGAGACUGAACAGUUCUGCUUCAGUAAUGAGCCUCUGGCUGGAGUCAUUGAGUGCUGCUAAAUCAGAAGUGUCCAGGUUGUGGGCUUUAGGUGGGAGCAACAGCGUCUGUCAGUUGAUUUCAUUUCUUUCUAGUAAUUUUCACAAUUCGCUCUUAUUGUUACAUUAAACUAAACCUCAGCAACAGUAGUAUUCAGGCUGAGACUAUUCUCUUGUUCUGAACGUUUGGGUUUGUUUUUUCAGCUUCCAUUUCUAGCUUUACUAAAUAAAAAUGUUGCAUGAAUAUUCUCAGCACUGGAAUUUGAAGUAGGAAGAAAGCUGAAGUCGACAUGUCUUUGUUUUCAACUAAGAUUUAGUGUUUUCUGGGGAGGAGUAUGGUAAAGUUGGUAAGAGUAUGCAUUUUUGAUAUCAGGCCUGGAUUUGGUUCUCAGCUCUACCAUUCACCACCUGUAUCACCUUAGACAAAUAAUCUAACUCCUCUGGACCUCAACUUCAUCUGUAAACAGAUAAUAUUUCUCAUAGGGUCAAUGAUCAUGUAAAUUAGAUAAUAUCCAUAAAAGGAAUAUAAUACAUGAUUGGUUGUUUCAUUAUGGAUGGAGGGGAUGAUGGUAACCUUAUUAUCAAAAAGAGGUUUGUGUCUGAGGCAGAACUAGAUGAACGGCGCAAAAGGAGGCAAGAAGAAUGGGAGAAAGUUCGAAAACCUGAAGAUCCAGAAGAAUGUCCAGAGGAGGUUUAUGACCCUCGAUCUCUAUAUGAAAGGCUACAGGAACAGAAGGACAGGAAGCAGCAGGAGUACGAGGAACAGUUCAAAUUCAAAAACAUGGUAAGAGGCUUAGAUGAAGAUGAGACCAACUUCCUUGAUGAGGUUUCUCGACAGCAGGAACUAAUAGAAAAGCAACGAAGAGAAGAAGAACUGAAAGAACUGAAGGAAUACAGAAAUAACCUCAAGAAGGUUGGAAUUUCUCAAGAGAACAAGAAGGAAGUGGAAAAGAAACUGACUGUGAAGCCUAUAGAAACCAAGAACAAGUUCUCCCAGGCGAAGCUGUUGGCAGGAGCUGUGAAGCAUAAGAGCUCAGAGAGUGGCAACAGUGUGAAAAGACUGAAACCGGACCCUGAGCCAGAUGACAAGAAUCAAGAGCCCUCAUCCUGCAAGUCUCUCGGAAACACCUCCCUGAGUGGCCCCUCCAUCCACUGCCCCUCUGCUGCAGUAUGUAUCGGCAUCCUCCCAGGCCUGGGUGCCUACUCUGGGAGCAGCGACUCCGAGUCCAGCUCAGACAGCGAAGGCACCAUCAAUGCCACCGGAAAGAUUGUCUCCUCCAUCUUCCGAACCAACACCUUCCUCGAGGCCCCCUAGUUUCUCCGUCCCUACACAGGGAGCUCCUCCCCAAGGGUAGAUCGGACCGUUCAUGCUGCCUAUAGGCAUUAUGUCCCUCAAAAAAAAACUCCUUUGCCUGCAUCCUGUGUACAACAUGACAUUUUUAACCAAUCCAAUCUAAAAAUGUGCCAGAAUCCACCUGUGGCCCGAAUCGUGUUUGGUUCCUCUUUCUACUCCACUGCAGAUGACCAAACCUGUCCCGCUGCCACUUUCCUCACUGAUAUUGGGAGGAGGGCAAGGCCCAGCCGAAGUUCCACUAAAAAUGCCCCAGGAGAAUAGGCACCGGCUGGCUUGCCAAAGGGUUUGGGUUUUAUUGCUUUCUGUUUUUUCUUUUCCCGACAGCACAAAGAAGUAAGGGCAGUUAUUGGACAGGUGUUAUUUAAACAUUCUAUUGUAAAUGAAUGUGUUGUUUGGUUCUACUGCAUUGUGGAGCAUGCGGGGGAAGAGAACUGACCCAGGUAGUGAAAUGGAGCCCUUCCCUGGAACUAACCAGUCCUUGAUGUUGUGUGACUAAGUAAAGAUGAUAAACCCCAUCUGCUGGGGGUGUCACUUCACACUCGGCAUGCAUUGUGAAAGCUUUCCAUACCCUUGGCCAUUCCCUCUCUCCUCUCUCUCCAACCCCAUUUAUGCAGGAAGGGACUGCUAACAAGAACGCUUCCAUCUCAAACCUUUUCUCUGCCUGGGAAAUUAUUUUAUGUUUGUUUUUGAAAUAAAGGAUUUAGUUUAAGAUUCUAAAUUUUAGAGAAACAAACGUAGGCCUUGUUUACUAAUAGCCAGACAUCAGAACUGCAGGUAGGUAUGUUAAUGAGAUGACUUAUUUCUGGCAGCUCCUGGAAUCCUAAUAUUGUAAAUGAGUGGGACACACUUGCAUAUUGUGACCAUUCUAUUGAGGCCCUUCUCUGUUUAAUGCAUAUUAUACUUGUGCUUUUAACUGUGGAAUCUAUUUCUAACCUAAAGGUGCUGCCCUAGUACUUUUCUUUGCUGCCUCUGCUGCUCUUUUUCCUUUCCAAACAGCAACUCUGAGGCCAUGAGCAGCCAAAAACUAGAGGUACUGCUCCACCUCGUCUCAUAAAGGGAAACGGGCUCAUCCCUUGGAUUCUGGAGGAGGGAGAGGGAGAUGGUGUGGAGGCCUCGAGGACAGAGAUAGACAUGAGCUUUGACAACAAUCUGUAGGCUCUCCUGCUUUAGAAUAAGCAUGUACCAUUCUUUAUCCAUUCCCCUUAUUCCUACAUCAAUUGUUUUUACUUUCUUGGGUGUGAGACUGAGUGAGACACACACAAAAUGUGUUGACACUGUGAUGCCGGCAGGCAGAGCAGCUACUGACUUUGAACAUGGGCAGAGAGGCCCCUGGAUCUCAUCCAGCCCACUCCUUUUCCCCUUCCAGUACAGUGACACUCUGGUGCCCAUUGGCAGAUGGCGACUUCCCUGCACCCAUAACUGAUGCUUUGUGAAUUCUUCCUCCUUUUCAGAACUACUCUGUGCUAAUUGUUCUGCCAGUAUGGGCGCAUCAGCUCCAUCCUGACAAACAAGACAUUUAGGUAAAACUUUGUAGGCACCUUCUGCUUCUCUGCUUCAUUGUUCCUGUGAUAGUCCUGUUGUUAUUACAGCAUGUACCCAAAACAGCCUCACAUUGUUACAGGAGGCAGGCCAGGACAUCAAAGUCAUCAUCUUUAUGUGGCAUGACUCUUAAGAGGCCAUUACUGUAUCUCAUGGCCUCUUGAUGUGGAAAGAAGUUGACAGAGGGUUGCAGGGUUUAAAAACAUCCAUUAACAUGAAAGCUAAUAAACCUGUCAGAGAACAAGA